GUCAUUGGCGGCUCCCAAGAUGGCGUCCAUCAUGGAAGGGCCGCUGAGCAAAUGGACUAACGUGAUGAAGGGCUGGCAGUACCGUUGGUUCGUGCUGGACUACAAUGCAGGACUGCUCUCCUACUACACGUCCAAGGACAAAAUGAUGAGAGGCUCUCGCAGAGGAUGUGUUAGACUCAGAGGAGCUGUGAUUGGUAUAGACGAUGAGGACGACAGCACCUUCACAAUAACUGUUGAUCAGAAAACCUUCCAUUUCCAGGCCCGUGAUGCUGAUGAGCGAGAGAAGUGGAUCCAUGCCUUAGAAGAAACAAUUCUUCGACAUACUCUCCAGCUUCAAGGUUUGGAUUCAGGAUUUGUUCCUAGUGUCCAAGAUUUUGAUAAGAAACUUACAGAAGCUGAUGCUUACCUACAAAUCUUGAUUGAACAAUUAAAGCUUUUUGAUGACAAGCUUCAAAACUGCAAAGAAGAUGAACAGAGAAAGAAAAUUGAAACUCUCAAAGAGACAACAAAUAGCAUGGUAGAAUCAAUUAAACACUGCAUUGUGUUGCUGCAGAUUGCCAAAAGUACAAUCUUGGUGAGGAAUUUGCUCGUCUUACCACUUGUAUUAGUCUGCAUGGGCUGCCAUAACAAAAUACCAUAGACUGGGUGGCUUAAAGAACAGAAGUUUAUUUUCUCACCGUUCUGGAAGCCAGAAGUCCAAGAUCAACAUUCUGGCCUGUUCAGUUUCUGAUGAGGGUCCUUCUCUUGGCCUGUAGAUAGCCAUGUCUUCACAUAGUCUUUCCUUGAGUACUAUUAAUCCCGUAGAUGCAAUAUAUCAACCUAGUCCUUUGGAACCUGUGAUCAGCACAAUGCCUUCCCAGACUGUGUUACCUCCAGAACCUGUUCAGUUGUGUAAGUCAGAGCAGCGUCCAUCUUCCCUACCAGUUGGACCUGUGUUGGCUACCUUGGGACAUCAUCAGACUCCUACACCAAAUAGUACAGGCAGUGGCCAUUCACCACCGAGUAGCAGUCUCACUUCUCCAAGCCACGUGAACUUGUCUCCAAAUACAGUCCCAGAGUUCUCUUACUCCAGCAGUGAAGAUGAAUUUUAUGAUGCUGAUGAAUUCCAUCAAAGUGGCUCAUCCCCAAAGCGCUUAAUAGAUUCUUCUGGAUCUGCCUCAGUCCUGACACACAGCAGCUCGGGAAAUAGUCUAAAACGCCCAGAUACCACAGAAUCACUUAAUUCUUCCUUGUCCAAUGGAACAAGUGAUGCUGACCUGUUUGAUUCACAUGAUGACAGAGAUGAUGAUGCGGAGGCAGGGUCUGUGGAGGAGCACAAGAGCGUUAUCAUGCAUCUCUUGUCGCAGGUUAGACUUGGAAUGGAUCUUACUAAGGUAGUUCUUCCAACGUUUAUUCUUGAAAGAAGAUCUCUUUUAGAAAUGUAUGCAGACUUUUUUGCACAUCCGGACCUGUUUGUGAGCAUUAGUGACCAGAAGGAUCCCAAGGAUCGAAUGGUUCAGGUUGUGAAAUGGUACCUCUCAGCCUUUCAUGCGGGAAGGAAAGGAUCAGUUGCCAAAAAGCCAUACAAUCCCAUUUUGGGCGAGAUUUUUCAGUGUCAUUGGACAUUACCAAAUGAUACUGAAGAGAACACAGAACUAGUUUCAGAAGGACCAGUUCCCUGGGUUUCCAAAAACAGUGUAACAUUUGUGGCUGAGCAGGUUUCCCAUCAUCCACCCAUUUCAGCCUUUUAUGCUGAGUGUUUUAACAAGAAGAUACAAUUCAAUGCUCAUAUCUGGACCAAAUCAAAAUUCCUUGGGAUGUCAAUUGGGGUGCACAACAUAGGGCAGGGCUGUGUCUCAUGUCUAGACUAUGAUGAACAUUACAUUCUCACAUUCCCCAAUGGCUAUGGAAGGUCUAUCCUCACAGUGCCCUGGGUGGAAUUAGGAGGAGAAUGCAAUAUUAAUUGUUCCAAAACAGGCUAUAGUGCAAAUAUCAUCUUCCACACUAAACCCUUCUAUGGGGGCAAGAAGCACAGAAUUACUGCCGAGAUUUUUUCUCCAAAUGACAAGAAGUCUUUUUGCUCAAUUGAAGGGGAAUGGAAUGGUGUGAUGUAUGCAAAAUAUGCAACAGGGGAAAAUACAGUCUUUGUAGAUACCAAGAAGUUGCCUAUAAUCAAGAAGAAAGUGAGGAAGUUGGAAGAUCAGAACGAGUAUGAAUCCCGCAGCCUUUGGAAGGAUGUCACUUUCAACUUAAAAAUCAGAGACAUUGAUGCAGCAACUGAAGCAAAGCACAGGCUUGAAGAAAGACAAAGAGCAGAAGCCCGAGAAAGGAAGGAGAAGGAAAUUCAGUGGGAGACAAGGUUAUUUCAUGAAGAUGGAGAAUGCUGGGUUUAUGAUGAACCAUUACUGAAACGUCUUGGUGCUGCCAAGCAUUAGGUUGGAAGAUGCAAAGUUUAUACCUGAUGAUCAGGGCAGUAGGCAUAAUUCAGCAACAAACAAUCUUCCUUUGGGAGAAACCUGUUCAUUCCAAUCUUCUAAUUACAGUGGUUCCUAUCUCAGGGAUACUGGACUUUCUGACGCAGAUGAACAAUUAAGGGGAAAAGCUUCCCUUUUCCCUCUGUGGCAGUUACGAUUUUGACUUCAGUCCUGAGAAAAACUUCAGGUUUUGAAAAUCAGAUGAUGUCUUCUCCUUUUCCAAACACCACACGUUGAAAGCAUUUAUAAAUCCAAGUCUGAAACUCUGCGCUCUAGUACUGCUGUUAAGAUACACAACUUGUUUCUUAGUUCAUAUAAUCUCGGGAUACACACACACACACACAUAUAUAUACACACACAUACGUAUACACACACAUACAUAUAUAUAAAUAUACCUGAUGCCAGAUUUUUUUCAUAAAUAUUCUGCCUACUGUAAAUAUGGGUUCCUCUGAGUUGUUUUAGAAAAUUAGCGCAAUGUAUUAAAAUCAAGUGUUAGGAAAUUUCAUGGUCUUACCUACAAUAACUUUUAUUUUGGAAUUGAACUAUUAUUAAAUUGUAUCUAAUCCUGGAUUACAGUUUAAUUAAUUAUUCUUAGUGCUUAAGGCUUCAUAAAGUAAUUUUUCCAACCUUUUUUUUAAAAAUGUGCAUCUUUUAUUAUCUUUUAUGGUUAAACUUGGAAGCCAAUUAUUUGGCAACCUUGAAUACAAGAGCUAGCUUUUCAAAGAAAGACACUUGAAAUAAUGGAGGAUCCAUUCUUUUCCUCUGUCAGAUUGUAUGUUCUGUCUUUAGCCCCUGCCAGGCAAUUCCCCAGAAUCUUCACUUAACUCAUAUUGCACAUGUAGGGCUGCCUACCAACAUUUUAUCCAAAAAUGUUUUAUUGCCUUAGAGGGUUUGGGAAGAGUGUGUAUUUAUAGAUCCCCACCCCACAGUGAACAAAAAUAGAUAGAUAGAUAGAAUAAAAUGAAUGCCACAGCAGCAGAUGGCUCAUUCUGAAGGGAAAUACAGAACUAUAUCUAUCUAUCUAUCUAUCAUCUUUUUUAUUUAAAAAUACAUUAAAAAAACAGGUAUUAGUACCUAGCAUUUAGUUAGUUAUUCAAUAUACUGGUUACGUAAGGCCUUUCAAGAAGUAGAUUCUCAGUCUGAGAGGACACAGGCCAGGGCUUCUCAAAGUGCUGCUGCAGGCUUUCUGGUCUCGCUUGGCCCAUUCUGCUAAUUUUCCUUUGCCAGCUCCUACAGUAACCCUGGGUUUAUUAGUCUCAACAAAGGAUAAAAAGUAAAUCAAAUGCUAUGAUGCCAGUGCAAAACUUCAAUGGAAGCCCUAAGGCAGUAGUAUAACUAACUCCAUAAAAUACAAACAAACACAUUUUAAAAUACACAUUGCUUCAGGCCAA